GUGGGAGCCGAACGCCGCGGGGUCAGGGCGUGCAGUCUGGGACGCGGGAUGCUUGGCGCUCUACCUCGCCGCCCCUGAGCCUUCCCGUCCGCCUCGCCACGCGCCCGGACGGCCUGGGGUUGCUGCCCGUCAGUCUCGAAAGGUGUUUUUGGGGAAAAAAAUCACAAUCUGGACGUGAGAAAGGACAUGAGGAGACUAAAGACCUGGGAUUUUGUCAAUCAGAAUGAAACCAAUGUUGAAAGACUUUUCAAAUCUAUUGUUGGUGGUACUCUGUGACUAUGUUCUUGGAGAAGCUGAAUAUCUUCUCUUGAGAGAGCCAGGCCAUGUAGCACUAAGCAACGACACAGUGUAUGUGGAUUUCCAGUAUUUUGAUGGUGCUAAUGGGACACUGAGGAAUGUAUCUGUCCUGCUGUUGGAGGCCAACACCAAUCAGACUGUAACUACCAAGUACCUCCUGACCAACCAGUCCCAGGGAACACUAAAGUUUGAGUGCUUCUAUUUCAAGGAGGCUGGUGACUACUGGUUCACAAUGACUCCAGAAGCAACAGACAACAGCACUCCAUUCCCCUGGUGGGAGAAAAGUGCCUUUCUGAAGGUGGAAUGGCCUGUCUUUCACGUUGACUUGAAUAGGAGUGCCAAGGCAGCAGAAGGCACCUUCCAAGUGGGCCUAUUUACCAGUCAACCACUGUGCCCGUUUCCUGUGGACAAGCCCAACAUCGUAGUGGAUGUCAUCUUCACCAACAGUCUUCCUGAGGCAAGAAGAAAUUCAAGACAGCCGCUGGAAAUAAGAACCAGCAAAAGGACAGAACUUGCUCAAGGUCAGUGGGUUGAGUUUGGCUGUGCACCCUUGGGGCCAGAAGCCUAUGUCACCGUGGUGCUGAAGCUGCUUGGGCGAGACUCAGUCAUUACCUCCACAGGACCCAUUGACCUGGCCCAGAAAUUUGGAUACAAACUGGUGAUGGUGCCAGAACUCACAUGUGAGUCCGGGGUAGAGGUGACAGUGCUGCCUCCACCAUGCACCUUCGUCCAAGGAGUGGUCACUGUCUUCAAGGAGGCCCCCAGAUACCCUGGGAAGAGGACCAUUCACUUGGCUGAAAACAGCCUGCCCCUGGGAGAGAGGAGGACAAUUUUUAACUGUACUUUGUUUGACAUGGGGAAGAAUAAGUACUGCUUUGACUUUGGCAUUUCAAGCAGAAGCCAUUUUUCUGCAAAGGAGGAGUGCAUGCUAAUUCAGAGAAAUACAGAAACUUGGGGACUGUGGCAGCCAUGGAGCCAGUGUAGUGCCACAUGUGGGGAUGGUGUCAGAGAGCGUCGCCGAGUGUGUCUCACUUCCUUCCCCUCCAGUCCUGUCUGCCCUGGAAUGUCCUUGGAGGCCUCCCUGUGUUCCCUGGAGGAGUGUGCUGCUUUCCAGCCAUCCAGCCCAUCUCCUCUUCAGCCCCAGGGUCCAGUGAAGUCCAACAACAUCGUGACUGUCACUGGUAUAUCCUUGUGCUUGUUCAUCAUCAUUGCCACUGUGCUCAUCACGCUGUGGAGGAGGUUCGGCCGGCCAGCCAAGUGCAGCACACCUGCUCGACACAACUCCAUCCACUCCCCCAGCUUCCGGAAGAACUCGGACGAGGAGAAUAUCUGCGAGCUGAGCGAGCAGCGCGGGAGCUUCUCGGAUGGGGGAGACGGGCCCACGGGGAGUCCAGGGGACACAGGCAUCCCUCUGACCUACAGGCGGAGCGGGCCGGUACCUCCCGAGGAUGAUGCCUCUGGCAGCGAGAGCUUCCAGUCCAACGCCCAGAAGAUAAUCCCACCUCUGUUCAGCUACCGCCUUGCCCAGCAGCAGUUAAAGGAGAUGAAAAAGAAAGGUCUGACGGAAACUACCAAAGUGUAUCACGUGUCUCAGAGUCCCCUGACAGACACUGCCAUUGAUGCGGCCCCCAGCGCUCCCUUAGAUUUGGAAAGCCCGGAAGAAGCUGCAGCAAACAAGUUCCGGAUCAAAUCCCCAUUUCCGGAGCAGCCCGCGGUCAGUGCCGGGGAAAGGCCUCCCUCCAGGCUGGAUCUAAAUGUGACUCAGGCCAGUUGUGCCAUAAGCCCCAGCCAGACUCUGAUCCGCAAGUCACAGGCAAGGCACGUGGGCAGCAGAGGGGGCCCGUCCGAAAGGAGCCAUGCCAGGAACGCCCAUUUCAGGAGGACAGCGAGUUUCCAUGAAGCCAGGCAGGCCCGGCCGUUCCGAGAGAGGAGCAUGUCCACUCUGACUCCACGGCAGGCCCCUGCCUACAGCUCUAGGACGCGGACCUGCGAGCAGGCAGAGGACAGAUUUAGGCCUCAGAGUCGAGGUGCCCACCUGUUUCCUGAAAAACUGGAGCAUUUCCAAGAGGCAAGUGGAACCCGUGGUCCAUUAAACCCUCUCCCUAAAUCCUACACUUUGGGGCAGCCCUUGAGGAAACCAGACCUUGGGGAUCACCAGGCAGGAUUAGUGGCCGGAAUUGAGAGAACAGAGCCCCACAGAGCUCGUCGGGGACCGUCCCCCAGUCACAAGAGUGUCUCAAGGAAGCAGUCUUCUCCCAUAUCCCCCAAAGAUAACUACCAGAGGGUCAGUUCUCUGAGCCCUUCUCAGUGUAGAAAAGACAAGUGUCAAAGCUUCCCCACUCACCCUGAGUUUGCCUUCUAUGACAAUACGUCGUUUGGCCUCACUGAGGCUGAGCAGAGGAUGCUGGACCUCCCAGGAUAUUUUGGGUCAAAUGAAGAGGAUGAAACCACAAGUACACUUAGCGUGGAGAAGCUGGUGAUCUAGACUGAGAAUCAGCCUGAGCUUUACACAGCUGGGGUCUGCUACUCGCGUUUUGUAGACUUUUGUGUAACUAUUUGUACCGUAGGACAGAAUGUGAGGAGGAAGUAACACACAGAGGAGGAUGUGUGUGUAUGCAUGUGUUUGAAUUCACAAGGAAGAAAUUAUUUAUCUUGAGCUUUUUCCUUUGUUAUUCAAUUUCUAUUGAUUUAUUAGUAAUAACAAUGAUAAUAAAAUGUAAAUGAGCAAA